GUAUCCCGCGCCUCCCGACCUUUGGCCGCUGGCAUUCCUGCGCGGGCGGGAGCUGCGGGCGCUCGGGGGAUAAGGCGAGGACGCACCAGCAUUAAUGGAAUAGGAGAACUCCCGAAGCUUUUAGGGCCCUGGGAAAGGGGGCGUGGCUGGAAACGGAGCUACUGGCUUCGGAGAAUUCUGUGACCCUCACCACCGCGACGACCCCGAGGAAACGCUGUCAGGUCGCCUUUGGUUGGCAAGGCGUGGUUGUCCUCGCUGUCCCGCGCCUUGGCGGAAUGGGCACCUCACUAGCCCUGGCACUAGCUAGCAUCGCUCUAAACUCAAGAGGCCUGAAUAUUUGGACAAGAUGGCAGAUUCAUCAUCAUCUUCUUUCUUUCCUGAUUUUGGGCUGCUAUUGUAUUUGGAGGAGCUAAACAAAGAGGAAUUAAAUACAUUCAAGUUAUUCCUAAAGGAGACCAUGGAACCUGAGCAUGGCCUGACACCCUGGAAUGAAGUGAAGAAGGCCAGGCGGGAGGACCUGGCCAAUUUGAUGAAGAAAUAUUAUCCAGGAGAGAAAGCCUGGAGUGUGUCUCUCAAAAUCUUUGGCAAGAUGAACCUGAAGGAUCUGUGUGAGAGAGCGAAAGAAGAGAUCAACUGGUCGGCCCAGACUAUAGGACCAGAUGAUGCCAAGGCUGGAGAGACACAAGAAGAUCAGGAGGCAGUGCUGGGUGAUGGAACAGAAUACAGAAAUAGAAUAAAGGAAAAAUUUUGCAUCACUUGGGACAAGAAGUCUUUGGCUGGAAAGCCUGAAGAUUUCCAUCAUGGAAUUGCAGAGAAAGAUAGAAAACUGUUGGAACACUUGUUCGAUGUGGAUGUCAAAACCGGUGCACAGCCACAGAUCGUGGUGCUUCAGGGAGCUGCUGGAGUUGGGAAAACAACCUUGGUGAGAAAGGCAAUGUUAGAUUGGGCAGAGGGCAGUCUCUACCAGCAGAGGUUUAAGUAUGUUUUUUAUCUCAAUGGGAGAGAAAUUAACCAGCUGAAAGAGAGAAGCUUUGCUCAAUUGAUAUCAAAGGACUGGCCCAGCACAGAAGGCCCCAUUGAAGAAAUCAUGUACCAGCCAAGUAGCCUCUUGUUUAUUAUUGACAGUUUCGAUGAACUGAACUUUGCCUUUGAAGAACCUGAGUUUGCACUGUGCGAAGACUGGACCCAAGAACACCCAGUGUCCUUCCUCAUGAGUAGUUUGCUGAGGAAAGUGAUGCUCCCUGAGGCAUCCUUAUUGGUGACAACAAGACUCACAACUUCUAAGAGACUAAAGCAGUUGUUGAAGAAUCACCAUUAUGUAGAGCUACUAGGAAUGUCUGAGGAUGCAAGAGAGGAGUAUAUUUACCAGUUUUUUGAAGAUAAGAGGUGGGCCAUGAAAGUAUUCAGUUCACUAAAAAGCAAUGAGAUGCUGUUUAGCAUGUGCCAAGUCCCCCUAGUGUGCUGGGCCGCUUGUACUUGUCUGAAGCAGCAAAUGGAGAAGGGUGGUGAUGUCACAUUGACCUGCCAAACAACCACAGCUCUGUUUACCUGCUAUAUUUCUAGCUUGUUCACACCAGUAGAUGGAGGCUCUCCUAGUCUACCCAACCAAGCCCAGCUGAGAAGACUGUGCCAAGUCGCUGCCAAAGGAAUAUGGACUAUGACUUACGUGUUUUACAGAGAAAAUCUCAGAAGGCUUGGGUUAACUCAAUCUGAUGUCUCUAGUUUUAUGGACAGCAAUAUUAUUCAGAAGGACGCAGAGUAUGAAAACUGCUAUGUGUUCACCCACCUUCAUGUUCAGGAGUUUUUUGCAGCUAUGUUCUAUAUGUUGAAAGGCAGUUGGGAAGCUGGGAACCCUUCCUGCCAGCCUUUUGAAGAUUUGAAGUCAUUACUUCAAAGCACAAGUUAUAAAGACCCCCAUUUGACACAGAUGAAGUGCUUUUUGUUUGGCCUUUUGAAUGAAGAUCGAGUAAAACAACUGGAGAGGACUUUUAACUGUAAAAUGUCACUGAAGAUAAAAUCAAAGUUACUUCAGUGUAUGGAAGUAUUAGGAAACAGUGACUAUUCUCCAUCACAGCUGGGAUUUCUGGAGUUGUUUCACUGUCUGUAUGAGACUCAAGAUAAAGCGUUUAUAAGCCAGGCAAUGAGAUGUUUCCCAAAGGUUGCCAUUAAUAUUUGUGAGAAAAUACAUUUGCUUGUAUCUUCUUUCUGCCUUAAGCACUGCCGGUGUUUGCGGACCAUCAGGCUGUCUGUAACUGUGGUAUUUGAGAAGAAGAUAUUAAAAACAAGCCUCCCAACUAACACUUGGGAUGGUGAUCGCAUUACUCACUGUUGGCAAGAUCUCUGUUCUGUGCUUCAUACAAAUGAACACUUGAGAGAAUUGGACCUGUACCAUAGCAACCUUGAUAAAUCAGCAAUGAAUAUCCUGCAUCAUGAACUAAGGCACCCAAACUGUAAACUACAAAAGCUACUGUUGAAAUUUAUCACUUUCCCUGAUGGUUGUCAGGAUAUCUCUACUUCUUUGAUUCAUAACAAGAAUCUGAUGCAUCUUGACCUAAAAGGGAGUGAUAUAGGGGAUAAUGGAGUAAAGUCAUUGUGUGAGGCCUUGAAACACCCAGAGUGUAAACUACAGACUCUCAGCUUAGAAAGCUGUGGUCUCACAGAGGCUGGCUGUGAGUAUCUUUCUUUGGCUCUCAUCAGCAAUAAAAGACUGACACAUUUGUGCUUGGCAGACAAUGUCUUGGGUGAUGGUGGAGUAAAGCUUAUGAGUGAUGCCCUGCAACAUGCACAAUGUACUCUGAAGAGCCUUGUGCUGAGGCGUUGCCAUUUCACUUCACUUAGCAGUGAAUAUCUGUCAACUUCUCUUCUACACAACAAGAGCCUGACGCAUCUGGAUCUAGGAUCAAACUGGCUACAAGACAAUGGAGUGAAGCUUCUGUGUGAUGUCUUUCGGCAUCCAAGCUGUAAUCUUCAGGACUUGGAAUUGAUGGGCUGUGUUCUCACUAAUGCAUGUUGUCUGGAUCUGGCUUCUGUUAUUUUGAAUAACCCAAACCUGAGGAGCCUGGACCUUGGGAACAACGAUUUGCAGGAUGAUGGAGUGAAAAUUCUGUGUGAUGCUUUGAGAUAUCCAAACUGUAACAUUCAGAGGCUCGGGUUGGAAUACUGUGGUUUGACAUCUCUCUGCUGUCAAGAUCUCUCCUCUGCUCUUAUCUGCAACAAAAGACUGAUAAAAAUGAAUCUGACACAGAAUACCUUAGGAUAUGAAGGAAUUGUGAAGUUAUAUAAAGUCUUGAAGUCUCCUAAGUGUAAACUACAAGUUCUAGGGAGGCCAUUGAAGCCGUUAAGACCGGGUCAGGUGAACAGGAAGUUAAAGACUGAAAAGGAGACACAAAACUGCCGACUUUCCCGACGGCGAAUUGGCCCUCUGGAAACAGCCGACCAAUCACAGGCAGCAGGGGCGCGCCCUGCAGCGGGGCUCCGGCUGCGGUUCCGUGGACUCGGCGACUAGGCGCCGCCUGACCAGUAGGAGCCGCCCUCGACGAGCGAGCUCGAAGGCUGCGACUGGCGCCGCCUCACCGCCUCCCACCGCCACUGACCGACCGUUCGACCGGCAAACAUGGUUGAAGCGGAUCGCCCGGGGAAGCUGUUCAUUGGGGGCCUCAACCUCGAAACCGACGAGAAAGCCCUCGAAGCCGAGUUUGGCAAGUAUGGCCGCAUCGUCGAGGUGCUCCUGAUGAAAGACCGAGAAACCAACAAGUCGAGGGGCUUCGCGUUCGUCACCUUUGAAAGCCCCGCAGACGCCAAGGCCGCCGCCAGAGACAUGAACGGCAAGUCCCUGGAUGGUAAGGCCAUCAAGGUGGCCCAGGCCACCAAACCGGCGUUCGAGAGCAGCCGGCGGGGCCCGCCGCCUCCCCGCAGCCGCGGUCGCCCGAGGUUCCUGCGCGGAACCCGCGGGGGUGGCGGCGGCCCGCGGCGUUCCCCAUCCCGGGGCGGGCCCGAUGAUGACGGCGGCUACACGGCGGAUUUCGACCUGCGGCCCUCCAGGGCCCCGAUGCCCAUGAAGCGUGGGCCGCCGCCGCGCAGGGUCGGCCCACCCCCCAAGAGGGCCGCGCCGUCGGGCCCGGCUCGCAGCAGCGGCGGUGGAAUGCGCGGGAGGGCCCUGGCCGUGCGGGGGCGAGACGGCUACUCAGGCCCACCGCGCCGGGAGCCGCUGCCCCCGCGCCGCGACCCCUACCUGGGCCCGCGGGAUGAGGGCUACUCGUCCAGAGACGGCUACUCGAGCCGAGACUACCGCGAACCCCGGGGUUUUGCCCCCUCGCCCGGAGAGUACACCCACCGCGAUUACGGCCACUCCAGUGUCCGGGACGACUGUCCCUUGAGAGGCUACAGCGACCGAGACGGCUACGGAGGUCGCGACCGUGACUACGGGGAUCAUCUGAGCAGAGGCUCCCAUCGAGAGCCCUUUGAGAGCUACGGAGAGCUGCGCGGCGCCGCCCCAGGACGGGGGACACCGCCAUCUUACGGAGGAGGAGGCCGCUACGAGGAGUACCGGGGCUACUCACCCGAUGCCUACAGCGGCGGCCGCGACAGUUACAGCAGCAGUUAUGGCCGGAGCGACCGCUACUCGAGGGGCCGACACCGGGUGGGCAGACCAGAUCGUGGGCUCUCUCUGUCCAUGGAAAGGGGCUGCCCUCCCCAGCGUGAUUCUUACAGCCGGUCAGGCUGCAGGGUGCCCAGGGGCGGAGGCCGUCUAGGAGGCCGCUUGGAGAGAGGAGGAGGCCGGAGCAGAUACUAAGCAGGAACAGACUUGGGACCAAAAAUCCCUUUUCAACGAAACUAACAAAAAGAAGAACCUGUUGUAUGGUAACUACCCAAGGACUAGUACAAGGAAGAGUUGUUUUUACCUUUUAAGAAUUUCCUGUUAAGAUCGUCUCCAUUUUUAUGCUUUUGGGAGAAAAAACUUAAAAUUCGUUUAGUUUAGUUUUGGAAUUGUUAACGUUUCUUUCAACAAGCUCCUGUUAAAAGUAUAUGAACCUGAGUACUAGUCUUCUUACAUUUACAAGUAGAAAUUCGAUUAAUGGCUUCUUCCCUUGUAAAUUUUCUUGAUAAAUGAGGCAAACAGUUCUAAGAUCUUUGAUAAACAUCUGCUCACCUAAAAUGGAAAAACGGAUCAUUCUGCUCAUUUAAACCAACUAGAUUUUGGGUGGAGAGUGGGAGGGAUUGGUGUAUGCUACUCUUAAGAUUUCAGGGUAUCUUUCAAACUGAAUCUUUGUUUCCAGUAUUAAAAAGCAAACAACCAGCAACAACAACAACAAAAGUGAUUUAGAUCAAAUGUUUAUGUAAAGAAAAUUAUUUUCACUCAGUAAAUCUGAAAAGUAAAUGGAUAAUGUUGGCCA